ACAGUAGCUGACUGGUCACCCUGCCACCCAGUGCUCACACCCUCUGGCCAGUGCCUGGCUAUGGCCCGACUGCUCAGGUCUGCAACCUGGGAGCUGUUCCCCUGGAGGGGCUACUGCUCCCAGAAGGCAAAGGGAGAGCUCUGCAGGGACUUCGUAGAGGCUCUGAAGGCCGUGGUGGGCGGCUCCCACGUGUCCACUGCCGCGGUGGUCCGAGAGCAGCACGGGCGCGAUGAGUCGGUGCACAGGUGCGAACCUCCUGAUGCUGUGGUGUGGCCCCAGAACGUGGAGCAGGUCAGCCGGCUGGCAGCCCUGUGCUAUCGCCAAGGUGUGCCCAUCAUCCCAUUCGGCACCGGCACCGGGCUUGAGGGUGGCGUCUGUGCUGUGCAGGGCGGCGUCUGCGUUAACCUGACGCAUAUGGACCGAAUCCUGGAGCUGAACCAGGAGGACUUCUCUGUGGUGGUGGAGCCAGGUGUCACCCGCAAAGCCCUCAACGCCCACCUGCGGGACAGCGGCCUCUGGUUUCCCGUGGACCCAGGCGCGGACGCCUCUCUCUGUGGCAUGGCGGCCACCGGGGCGUCGGGGACCAACGCGGUCCGCUACGGCACCAUGCGGGACAACGUGCUCAACCUGGAGGUGGUGCUGCCCGACGGGCGGCUGCUGCACACGGCGGGCCGAGGCCGGCAUUUCCGCUUCGGCUUCUGGCCAGAAAUCCCUCAUCACACAGCCUGGUACUCACCUUGUGUGUCCCUGGGACGUAGGAAGAGUGCAGCCGGCUACAACCUCACGGGGCUCUUCGUGGGCUCCGAGGGGACGCUGGGCCUCAUCACAGCCACCACCCUGCGCCUGCACCCUGCCCCUGAGGCCACAGUGGCCGCCACGUGUGCGUUCCCCAGUGUCCAGGCUGCUGUGGACAGCACUGUACACAUCCUCCAGGCUGCAGUGCCCGUAGCCCGCAUUGAGUUCCUGGAUGAAGUCAUGAUGGAUGCCUGCAACAGGUACAGCAAGCUGAAUUGCUUAGUGGCGCCCACACUCUUCCUGGAGUUCCAUGGCUCCCAGCAGGCACUGGAGGAGCAGCUGCAGCGCACAGAGGAGAUAGUCCAGCAGAACGGAGCCUCUGACUUCUCCUGGGCCAAGGAGGCCGAGGAGCGCAGCCGGCUUUGGACAGCACGGCACAAUGCCUGGUACGCAGCCCUGGCCACGCGGCCAGGCUGCAAGGGCUACUCCACGGAUGUGUGUGUGCCCAUCUCCCGGCUGCCGGAGAUCGUGGUGCAGACCAAGGAGGAUCUGAAUGCCUCAGGACUCACAGGAAGCAUUGUCGGGCAUGUGGGUGACGGCAACUUCCACUGCAUCCUGCUGGUCAACCCUGAUGACGCCGAGGAACUGGGCAGGGUCAAGGCUUUUGCAGAACAGCUGGGCAGGCGGGCACUGGCUCUCCACGGAACGUGCACGGGGGAGCAUGGCAUCGGAAUGGGCAAGCGGCAGCUGCUGCAGGAGGAGGUGGGCGCCGUGGGCGUGGAGACCAUGCGGCAGCUCAAGGCCGUGCUAGACCCCCAAGGCCUCAUGAAUCCAGGCAAAGUGCUGUGAAGGGGGUCUGAGCACUUAGCCCACAAGUUCCCUGACUACGGAGCCGGUUCUGGAACUUUUCUUCAUGCCACGGCCCCUGCAAGGAAAUAGAUGCUGAGGCAGUCUUCCUGCCAGCGAGCCCACUGUAUCUGGGCCCAAGGCCAGAGGGCCCAGAGAGAAGCCUGAGCACCGUGUUACCUCCCUGGCCCUCUGGCUGGCCCCAGGAGCCUUUGGUUCAGUAAACGACCCAGGGUGGUUCCCAGCAAAGCUGCUUCCUCUCUGCUCCUACGCAUCCUGUCCUGGCGGGAAGAGAGCGUCUGGGUCCAUUCAAGACUCUGAUGACACCCCUCCCCGAGGCCUCCCACUGCCGGGGUCCCAGGACCCUUCCCCCUUCACCUGGUGACAGGAACACUCCUUUCCUGGUAUGGAACGUGAGCUCCCGUGACAUGAUGAUAGGUCUUCUCCUUGGGGCCUCCCCCAAUAAAUCUGUAAUAAACCUGAAACCCACCUACA